AAAUGUUUGGAUUUCUCCACCAGGAGGGAGGACAAACAAGCUUUCUUCUUGCCUUCUGGGCAGCUUUGUGUGCUCUCCAGCACGGAGUCCGAGGAGGAACAGCGAAGCUGAAAAUGAAAAUUACUCUGGCGCUGGACCCAAUCGCUCCUCUACGGCAUCAAUCUCAUCGGACCCCCCCACCCUACCGCCUCUCAGAAAUGACCACUUUUGCAAAAUUGCAUGCAUUUCCAAGCUUCAUCCGGCUCCAGGCUUGGCCUCUCCCAGAGGCAGGCGGCUUGUGAGACGGGCUCCAGAGAAAGGACCUCCCUGGGUCUCUCAUUUCCUGGCUGAAGUUUCUCUUCUCGCUGCUGUGGCAGCAUCCAACCCACACACACAGGACCCGCAUCCUGGGUGAUGAAGUCAGACACGCAGCAGCUGGGUGAGUGCUAACGCUCAGAUAAGCAUCUGUGCCAUUGUGGGGACUCCCUGGGCUGCUCUGCACCCGGACACUUGCUCUGUCCCCGCCAUGUACAACGGGUCGUGCUGCCGCAUCGAGGGGGACACCAUCUCCCAGGUGAUGCCGCCGCUGCUCAUUGUGGCCUUUGUGCUGGGCGCACUAGGCAAUGGGGUCGCCCUGUGUGGUUUCUGCUUCCACAUGAAGACCUGGAAGCCCAGCACUGUUUACCUUUUCAAUUUGGCCGUGGCUGAUUUCCUCCUUAUGAUCUGCCUGCCUUUUCGGACAGACUAUUACCUCAGACGUAGACACUGGGCUUUUGGGGACAUUCCCUGCCGAGUGGGGCUCUUCACGUUGGCCAUGAACAGGGCCGGGAGCAUCGUGUUCCUUACGGUGGUGGCUGCGGACAGGUAUUUCAAAGUGGUCCACCCCCACCACGCGGUGAACACUAUCUCCACCCGGGUGGCGGCUGGCAUCGUCUGCACCCUGUGGGCCCUGGUCAUCCUGGGAACAGUGUAUCUUUUGCUGGAGAACCAUCUCUGCGUGCAAGAGACGGCCGUCUCCUGUGAGAGCUUCAUCAUGGAGUCGGCCAAUGGCUGGCAUGACAUCAUGUUCCAGCUGGAGUUCUUUAUGCCCCUCGGCAUCAUCUUAUUUUGCUCCUUCAAGAUUGUUUGGAGCCUGAGGCGGAGGCAGCAGCUGGCCAGACAGGCUCGGAUGAAGAAGGCGACCCGGUUCAUCAUGGUGGUGGCAAUUGUGUUCAUCACAUGCUACCUGCCCAGCGUGUCUGCUAGACUCUAUUUCCUCUGGACGGUGCCCUCGAGUGCCUGCGAUCCCUCUGUCCAUGGGGCCCUGCACAUAACCCUCAGCUUCACCUACAUGAACAGCAUGCUGGAUCCCCUGGUGUAUUAUUUUUCAAGCCCCUCCUUUCCCAAAUUCUACAACAAGCUCAAAAUCUGCAGUCUGAAACCCAAGCAGCCAGGACACUCAAAAACACAAAGGCCGGAAGAGAUGCCAAUUUCGAACCUCGGUCGCAGGAGUUGCAUCAGUGUGGCAAAUAGUUUCCAAAGCCAGUCUGAUGGGCAAUGGGAUCCCCACAUUGUUGAGUGGCACUGAACAAGCAGACCAACAACACUGAGGAAGAUAGAGUGGUGACUUAGAAUUAACUCGUGCUAAGGGGUCGGGGGCUUUGAAAAUGCCACCCCCCUUUCUUAUUGCAAGACGGCUUCUCGCACAUGAACUGCAUCCUUCUCAUUCUGUCGGAAAUGAAAUUCACACAACUAUACCUUUUGGGGAGGUUCCAGUUGAUUGAAGUGAGUUGGCUGCAUUUUCUUAUCUGAUCACAAUGGCAGGGGACAGAAUGUGCAUGGAGUGGAGCAUGUGUGUGUUGGGAGGGGGGCUAGGAACUGCACAGCCCUUGUGUAAUUUUCGUUGUUUGUUUUUGUUUUGAGACAGAGUCUCACUCUGUGUCCCAGGCUGGAGUGCAGUGGCACAGUCUCGGCUCACUGCAACCUCUGCCUCCCGGGUUCAAGCAAUUCUCCUGCCUCAGCCUCCCGAGUAGCUGGGAUUAGAGGCGCCAGCCAACACACCCGGCUAAUUUUUGUAUUUUUAGUAGAGACAGGGUUUUGCCAUGUUGGCCAGGCUGGUCUCGAGCUCCUGACCUCAGGUGAUCCGCCUGCCUUGGCCUCCCAAAGUGGUGGGAUCACAGGCGUGAGCCACCGUGCCUGGCCUCCCCUGUGUCAUUUUAAAUGGCUAAGUAAAUGGGUAUAUGUGUUUGAAUGGGGCAUGUUCACUCUCUUAGGGGCUAUGGGGCAGUUAGCAGCAUUUCCUAUCCUCUGACCUUAAAUCAUUCCUUAUCUCAGAAAACAGAAACCGGGCUCAGUCAAUCAAUGCUUUAUUUCAGGCCGAAUGAGGCUCUUUAGAUUGGGAUCUAUUGAUCUAUCAAUUUUCAUCUUUACAUUUCUUUGUACAUCUGUACAUUUUGUCCAAAUGUACAUCUGUACGUCUGUCAUCAUUGUGACUUCCUGGUAGCCCAAGAAGAACAACAACAAAACAAUCUGCUCUGACCUUCUUCAAAUCUUUGUAUUUCAAAGAAGGUGCUGAGGGAUCUGUUUCCUUGCCCUGGCUUCUCCAGUGGGAUGUGCUGAGUCCAAUACAAUUGCUUUUAUAAUUGCUUUUGACAACUUGUCAUGUGACUGUGAAUUGAAAUUAUUCACUUAUUUUCCAAGUAUUUACUGAAUUCGUAUUUGGUGGCAGGCAGUAUACUGUGUAAUUUUUAGUGGAGGGUCAUUAGUCAACUCUUAUGUGACAGUAAAGUUUUUUGGGGGGGUGGGGACAGAGAAGUUAAGAGCUUUCAUCCUUUCACGGAAUACAGUUUCUAGACCGAUUCUGUGUGAACAUCAGUUUUGUCCUCUUAUUGCAAGACUCCCUCAUACACAUGAGUUUCCCAAAUGUGUACCUGGACCCCUCGAAACAGAGGACUCUACGAAAUGACAAGCUGCCCCUGCCCUGAAUUAGGGGGAAACAUUCCAGGCCAACUCUAGCUCCUUUCUCAAGCUACAAAGUGGUGAACAUGGUUCUCAACUCCUUAAUUUAUACUCUCUCAAAUGCCCAGGAUACUCUACCCACUUAAGAACCUUGCCAACUUCUGGGGGUUGGGCAUGGUGGCUCACGCUUGUGAUCCCAGCACUUUGGGAGACUGAGGCGGAUCACCUGAGGUCAGGAGUUCUAGACCAGCCUGACCAACAUGGAGAAACCUCGUCUCUACUAAAAAUUCAAAAUUAGCCUGGUGUGGUGGCGCAUGCCUAUAAUCCCAGCUAUUCGGGAGGCUGAGGCAGGAGAAUCACUUGAACCGAGGAGGUGGAGGUUGCGGUGAGGUGACAUCGUGCCAUUGCACUCCAGACUGGGCCACAGGAGUGAAACGCCGUCUCAAAAAAAAAAAAGAACUUUGCCAACUUCUAGUUCUUUGGCCUCAAAACACCCCUCUAGGCUGUCCCUAUUAUUCCUUUUUUCAGAGGCACUGUGCAGCCUAGUGAUGAAAAGUACGAGCUAUAGAGCAUUAGAAGCAUCGAAGUUUGAAUCUCAGCUCAAGCAUUUACUAGGCCUGUGAUCUUAGGGCAGCUUGUGUUUUUAGACACUGAAUCUUGCUCUGUUGCCCAGGCUGGAGUGCAGUGAGUGGCAUGAUCAUAGCUCACUGCAGCCUCAAACUCCUGGGCUCAAGUGUUCCUCCCACCUCAGCCUCCUGAAUAGCUGGGAGUACAGGCAUAAGCCACCACACUCAGCUAAUUUUUAAAUUUUUUUUAUAGAGACGAGGUCUCACUCACUGUGUUGCCCAAGCUGGUCUCAAACUCCUGGCCUCCAGCAAUCCUCCCACCUUGGCCUCCCAAAGUAUUGCGAUUGCCAGCAUGAGCCACUGCUCCCAGCCUGGCAUAUAUAUAGAUAUAUAUAGAGAUAUAUAGAUAUCUAUCUAUCUAUAUAUAUAUAUAUUUUUUUUUUUUUUUUUGAGACAGAGUCUUGCUCUAUCACCCAGGCUGGAGUACAGUGGCCCAAUCUCAGCUCACUGCAAGCUCUGCCUCCUGGGUCCACGCCAUUCUCCUGCCUCAGCCUCCAGAGUAGCUGGGACUACGGGCGCCCCACCACCACGCCCGGCUAAUUUUUUGUAUUUUUAGUACAGACGGGGUUUCAUUGUGUUAGCCGGGAUGGUCUUGAUCUCCUGACUUGUGAUCCGCCUGCCUCGGCCUCCCAAAGUGCUUGGAUUACAGGUGUAAGCCACCGCACCCCGCCCAGCCUGGCAGAUUUUAUUUAAUCAUUUGUAGCUUCAUUUUCCUCGUCUGUCAAACAGGGAUACUGUAAUACAACCUCAGUGUGUCAUUGGGCAGUUUAAAUGAAUGUACAUUCCUGAGGCAUCAGAACUUUGUUCACUGUUAUAUACCCAAUGCCUAGAAGAGGACCUGCACAUAGCAGGUGCUCAGUAAAUGUUUGUUGAAUGAAUGAUUAAGUGCAUGUAAAGCAUUAAGCAUAGCGCCUGGCAGUAAGUGCUCAAUAUUAUGACUUCUUAUAUUAACACGUUUUACAUAUAAAGAAAUGGAGGCAAGAAAGCAUUUCCUUUGGGGUUUAGAGCGCUUAAGUUGUUCCUCUGUUAUCAUGCCUGAAUUCCCCCGCCCCUCAGUUACCUGGGGAAGAGUAAAGGCAAGAAUUCUUACCAGCAUUAGUCAUACAUCCUCCUGAUAGGAAUCUGCGAAAACACACACUUCUGCUUUUAGUUCUAUUCUUAGAAUUCUCUCCUGGGCUGUUGCUCCUUUGUUCCUUCAUUGUAAUAAAAAUGGAUUCUGAAAGCAAA